CGUCUCUGCCUUCCCGGGCGUACCGGCCACCCUUUCGGGAGGCGGCGUGGGGGCGACCGCGGCCGGGGGCCGCAGGAGCGUUUGAAGCGGGGGUGUAGGCCUGGCCGGAGGCUGGCCGGAGCGGGAAGGGGGCGUGCGGCCGGGCGCGGGGUCGCAGUGGGUGCGCUCCCGGCCGCUGCGCGGCGCUUGGACCGGGCCCCGCCGAGAGGAGCGGCCGCCGCGGGACGCGGCACCUUUGCGGGCGAAGCUGCUCACUUCCAGGCGCGACUGUUACACAACACGCCUGCCAAGUGGGGCCCUGGCCUGACUGUUCCCAUUAUCCCCAGUUCGCCUUUGGUGUAAGCAGCGAGGCCACCUGGGUGGUGACGGUGCUGCUUUCUUCAACCAACCAACCGAAAAAGCCCUCAAUUUUCGGACAGGGGCUCGGGUCUUGGCGUUGGGGGGCCCGACGCCUAGUGACUUCUUUAUUUACACUAGCUGCAAAACGUGAGAAAUAAAAAAGCCCAGGGUCUGUGUAUCACGUGUAGUUUCAUGUAAUGAAACACCACAGAGGGAAAUAUUUUCAGAUGCUGGGUUUAUUUCCUAAAGAAUACCAAUAAUGAACCAGAGAAAAGGCAAGUAGAUCUGAAAAUGAAUGGAUACUGCAAAAUCCUAAAGAAGUUUAGGAAACAUCAACUGCAAGGAUUCUUGGCGUUUUGAAGUCGUGGGUGUCUCAGAUUGGAGAAAGCACACCUCUAACCAGCCUGUGAUGAAUAAGCUGGGGAGGAAAAAAACCUGUUGCAUAAUCUCAUUUGCCGUGGGGUUUGCUGUGCCAUCCCCUUGAACCAAAGGGAAGUGAGUUAAGAUGCAGGGUUUUAAAACUCUCUGAAGUUUUUAUUUACCCAGCGCUCUGGCUCCCACUUCUGUUUUAAAAGAUUAUAAGUAAAUACUCUGCUCUUUCAAGUGAACCAAACCUAUCAAACCUGUUUAGAAAAUAAACCAGGCAGAAUAAAAUGAUGCGAAAUGUUCAUUUUAAAAAACUUCAGGAUGGGCACAAACACACAGAAGUGGGAAAUGAAUAAAAGAGUAUUGAUAAAUUUUUGAAAAUUGUUGAAGCUGAGUAAUGGACAUGAGUUACCCAUUUUACAGAUGAGGAAACUAAGGCCUUAGAGAGAUGAAGUAAUUUAUUGAAAUCCUAAAGCAAGUAAGAAGUGGUGCUAGAAUUGGAGCCAAGAUCUUCUGAUUCAUAUUCAGGCUUUCAGUCCAGUGUAAAGCUGUUGGAGCGCGGGAGCAAAGGUAAAGAAUGAUGUAAUGCGCUGGCUGCUCCAAAGCAUCUUUUGUUGUGGAAUGGUUAUUCCAGUCAUCUCUUUAUGAAUCAAAUGUGAGGGGCUGCUUUGUGGACGGAGUCCUUUGCAAGAGCACAUCAACGGGAAAGAGAAAGAGACAUUCACUUGGAGGGCUCUUGCUGAAAAUGGGUUUAACUCUCCUUUUGCCAGUCACCACCAGCCUGACCUCAUACACUUUUAGUACAAUGGAGUGGCUGAGCCUUUGAGCACACCACCAUUACAUCAUCGUGGCAAAUUAAAGAAGGAGGUGGGAAAAGAGGACUUAUUGUUGUCAUGGCCCAUGAGAUGAUUGGAACUCAAAUUGUUACUGAGAGGUUGGUGGCUCUGCUGGAAAGUGGAACGGAAAAAGUGCUGCUAAUUGAUAGCCGGCCAUUUGUGGAAUACAAUACAUCCCACAUUUUGGAAGCCAUUAAUAUCAACUGCUCCAAGCUUAUGAAGCGAAGGUUGCAACAGGACAAAGUGUUAAUUACAGAGCUCAUCCAGCAUUCAGCGAAACAUAAGGUUGACAUUGAUUGCAGUCAGAAGGUUGUAGUUUACGAUCAAAGCUCCCAAGAUGUUGCCUCUCUCUCUUCAGACUGUUUUCUCACUGUACUUCUGGGUAAACUGGAGAAGAGCUUCAACUCUGUUCACCUGCUUGCAGGUGGGUUUGCUGAGUUCUCUCGUUGUUUCCCUGGCCUCUGUGAAGGAAAAUCCACUCUAGUCCCUACCUGCAUUUCUCAGCCUUGCUUACCUGUUGCCAACAUUGGGCCAACCCGAAUUCUUCCCAAUCUUUAUCUUGGCUGCCAGCGAGAUGUCCUCAACAAGGAGCUGAUGCAGCAGAAUGGGAUUGGUUAUGUGUUAAAUGCCAGCAAUACCUGUCCAAAGCCUGACUUUAUCCCCGAGUCUCAUUUCCUGCGUGUGCCUGUGAAUGACAGCUUUUGUGAGAAAAUUUUGCCGUGGUUGGACAAAUCAGUAGAUUUCAUUGAGAAAGCAAAAGCCUCCAAUGGAUGUGUUCUAGUGCACUGUUUAGCUGGGAUCUCCCGCUCCGCCACCAUCGCUAUCGCCUACAUCAUGAAGAGGAUGGACAUGUCUUUAGAUGAAGCUUACAGAUUUGUGAAAGAAAAAAGACCUACUAUAUCUCCAAACUUCAAUUUUCUGGGCCAACUCCUGGACUAUGAGAAGAAGAUUAAGAACCAGACUGGAGCAUCAGGGCCAAAGAGCAAACUCAAGCUGCUGCACCUGGAGAAGCCAAAUGAACCUGUCCCUGCUGUCUCAGAGGGUGGACAGAAAAGCGAGACGCCCCUCAGUCCACCCUGUGCCGACUCUGCUACCUCAGAGGCAGCAGGACAAAGGCCCGUGCAUCCCGCCAGCGUGCCCAGCGUGCCCAGCGUGCAGCCGUCGCUGUUAGAGGACAGCCCGCUGGUACAGGCGCUCAGUGGGCUGCACCUGUCCGCAGACAGGCUGGAAGACAGCAAUAAGCUCAAGCGUUCCUUCUCUCUGGAUAUCAAAUCAGUUUCAUAUUCAGCCAGCAUGGCAGCAUCCUUACAUGGCUUCUCCUCAUCAGAAGAUGCUUUGGAAUACUACAAACCUUCCACUACUCUGGAUGGGACCAACAAGCUAUGCCAGUUCUCCCCUGUUCAGGAACUAUCGGAGCAGACUCCCGAAACCAGUCCUGAUAAGGAGGAAGCCAGCAUCCCCAAGAAGCUGCAGACCGCCAGGCCUUCAGACAGCCAGAGCAAGCGAUUGCAUUCGGUCAGAACCAGCAGCAGUGGCACCGCCCAGAGGUCCCUUUUAUCUCCACUGCAUCGAAGUGGGAGCGUGGAGGACAAUUACCACACCAGCUUCCUUUUCGGCCUUUCCACCAGCCAGCAGCACCUCACGAAGUCUGCUGGCCUGGGCCUUAAGGGCUGGCACUCGGAUAUCUUGGCCCCCCAGACCUCUACCCCUUCCCUGACCAGCAGCUGGUAUUUUGCCACAGAGUCCUCACACUUCUACUCUGCCUCAGCCAUCUACGGAGGCAGUGCCAGUUACUCUGCCUACAGCUGCAGCCAGCUGCCCACUUGCGGAGACCAAGUCUAUUCUGUGCGCAGGCGGCAGAAGCCAAGUGACAGAGCUGACUCGCGGCGGAGCUGGCAUGAAGAGAGCCCCUUUGAAAAGCAGUUUAAACGCAGAAGCUGCCAAAUGGAAUUUGGAGAGAGCAUCAUGUCAGAGAACAGGUCACGGGAAGAGCUGGGGAAAGUGGGCAGUCAGUCUAGCUUUUCGGGCAGCAUGGAAAUCAUUGAGGUCUCCUGAGAAGAAAGACACUUGUGACUUCUAUAGACAAUUUUUUUUUCUUGUUCACAAAAAAAUUCCCUGUAAAUCUGAAAUAUAUAUAUGUACAUACAUAUAUAUUUUUGGAAAAUGGAGCUAUGGUGUAAAAGCAACAGGUGGAUCAACCCAGUUGUUACUCUCUUAACAUCUGCAUUUGAGAGAUCAGCUAAUACUUCUCUCAACAAAAAUGGAAGGGCAGAUGCUAGAAUCCCCCCUAGACGGAGGAAAACCAUUUUAUUCAGUGAAUUACACAUCCUCUUGUUCUUAAAAAAGCAAGUGUCUUUGGUGUUGGAGGACAAAAUCCCCUACCAUUUUCACGUUGUGCUACUAAGAGAUCUCAAAUAUUAGUCUUUGUCCGGACCCUUCCAUAGUACACCUUAGCGCUGAGACUGAGCCAGCUUGGGGGUCAGGUAGGUAGACCCUGUUAGGGACAGAGCCUAGUGGUAAAUCCAAGAGAAAUGAUCCUAUCCAAAGCUGAUUCACAAACCCACGCUCACCUGACAGCCGAGGGACACGAGCAUCACUCUGCUGGACGGACCAUUAGGGGCCUUGCCAAGGUCUACCUUAGAGCAAACCCAGUACCUCAGACAGGAAAGUCGGGGCUUUGACCACUACCAUAUCUGGUAGCCCAUUUUCUAGGCAUUGUGAAUAGGUAGGUAGCUAGUCACACUUUUCAGACCAAUUCAAACUGUCUAUGCACAAAAUUCCCGUGGGCCUAGAUGGAGAUAAUUUUUUUUUCUUCUCAGCUUUAUGAAGAGAAGGGAAACUGUCUAGGAUUCAGCUGAACCACCAGGAACCUGGCAACAUCACGAUUUAAGCUAAGGUUGGGAGGCUAACGAGUCUACCUCCCUCUUUGUAAAUCAAAGAAUUGUUUAAAAUGGGAUUGUCAAUCCUUUAAAUAAAGAUGAACUUGGUUUCAAGCCAAAUGUGAAUUUAUUUGGGUUGGUAGCAGAGCAGCAGCACCUUCAAAUUCUCAGCCAAAGCAGAUGUUUUUGCCCUUUCUGCUUCACUGCAUGGAUACAGUUGGUAAAAUGUAAUAAUAUGGCAGAAUUUUAUAGGAAACUUCCUAGGGAGGUAAAUUAUGGGAAGAUUAAGAAAGGUACAAAUUGCUGAGGAGAAGCAGGAAACCUGUUUCCUUAGUGGCUUUUAUCCCCUCGGCAUGCGAUGGGGCUGAUGUUUCUAUGAUUGCCUCAGACUUUCACAUUUACUAGUAGGGCUGAGAGAGGCUUUAGUGAGGAAGGAAUAUUCAGAAUAAAACGGUUGAGAAAGCUGAGAAGACCAUUGAGUUUUGAUCAGUUGUGAAUAGAGUGCAAAGCCAUGGCCAAGCUGUUUUUGGAAACGCUGGCCGGCGUGUCUUCAGUGGAAAAAGCAAAUCAAAAUGGAGCGAGAGCAAAGGGGCGUCCUCAGUCCUCAACCUACAAUCACUGUAUGGAAUCGGUCCUGGCAGCUGAACAUAGGAGGUCACUGGAACAAGUGAUAGUGCAGAUUGGCUUUCAAACAUCCUCCUGGCUUGAGUUUUAUCAGCUACAAUGUGGGUCCUCUUUUGAAGCCUUAAUUCACAACAGCAGCUUUUUGGGGGUGGGGCUGGGCGGGUGUUGUCAUUGUUCUUUCCCUUCCUGUAAGUGUCGCUAGUUGCUGCCUCGUAUCUCAGGUUUUUCUCUGUUUUUGAGAAAUGGACAGUUUUUUGACCAGGAUGUGACUUCAUGUUUCCUAUGGUGACUUCUAAAACCAGCACAGAAUGAUAUGACUCAACACAGACCGACUUGGUUAUGGGGAUGAUGAGCCGCACAGACCUCACUAGUUGUGCACAAAUAAUGUGCUAUGAUGGGGUGUAAAGUGAAGGCAGAAGAGGGUCAGCCGCAUUGUUAUGAUACUGGGAAAGUGCUGGUCAACGAUUUGAGUUAGUUUUUAGAUAUACAUUGAAAUCUUUAAUCAGACAUUCUCAAGUUUCACACAGUAGUUUUUGAUGUUAUGUACACACACACCAAAUGUGUAACAGUUCACCACUUCCAGAGUGUGGUCAUGCCCAAAACAUGUUUAAGAAAGGAAAGCAGUAGCUCCUUGCUAACGAUGUUUCAGGAGGUUUGGGGGACUUGGUUUUAAUGAGCUUCUGUCAUUUAGGGCUUCUCUUGGCCAUGGUCCCCCUUCCUUCUGGAACUGUGAUGUAGUCACAUCCUACAGCCUUUAGUGCUGGUUCACUAGUGUCAGAUAAUCAGUUCUUGGAAUCGAGACUGCCGUGGCGAAGGGGUGGCCUCGGAGGCAGGCUCUGGAGCUGCUUGGAUGUCUUUAGGUGGGGUGGUGGCUGGCUCUCUUCAGCAUGUAAUUGGGGAAACCCUCGCGUCUACUAGGGGUGAUACAGAUGGUGAUUUUAAAGAGCAAAACUAGACUUCUAUGUGAGAAGUGCUGGAAAAUGAUUUAGGACAUGUGUAAAGUUAGAUGGAAAGACUGUAAAUGUUUAAUAUGAAUAUAGUGUUCUUUUGAAGUAAGGCCAGCUGUUGAACGGUUAAACUGUGCAUUUCUCAUUUUGAUGUGUCAUGUAUGUUAAUGUAUGAAAUGAUUAAAUAAAAUCAAAACUGGUACCUGUUUAUACAUAAAUACGAGAAAAGACCUAUCUUUGCAGCCAUAAACUCGGUGGGAACACCACCACUCAAGUUGCCAAAGGAGGCAGUGGUGAAACCUGUCCUGUUCUCACUUAAAUGAGGAUUUAGCUCAAAAUAAAGUGGUGGUGUCAUCAGGUUUAUUCCGUGUUCUGUCAUUCACAUGGAACACCGGAUGAUUAGCUAACAGUUUAGUGCCAGCCUUCAUUCUUUACUGUGUACGUUAAAUGCACACUACAGUGAAAAAGCCUAAGACACUUGGUAAAUAUUUUCUAGCUGACUGAUUCCAGAACACACAAGUACAUGGUAGGAAAAAAAAGGCCAGCUACACACACAUGGCCCAUUUCGAUAUAACAUGUAAAUGAUGUUACGAUUCCUACAGGAAAAACAGGAAGGGCAAUUGUUGAAGAGCUGUCCUUUGUCCUUGCCACAUACAUCUCAACAACCUCUCUGCUCAUGACACUAGAUUUGAUGACUUAUGAGACUAGAAACUUAGUCUCAUCAGUUUCAUAAAAAUUAGGCAUUGAAGGAAUAAAGCUUCAGUGCAAACAGAUGGAAUAUUGACUACAGAAAGAAUCACAGGUGACCUUGAAGUUGGUUGAGUUGAAGUUACAUUUAAGAAAAUUUAUAAGAAAGAUUGGGCCGGGUGAGCUAGACUAGAAGAGCUAUCUUGGCCAGGACCCUGCAGAAAAAGAGGUGGAAGUGAGAUAGAGGAAUAAAGGGAAUUAGAAUAAAUCAGCCUCCAGAGAUAGAGGGUAACAGGAGGAACAGUUGUUUCAGUGAGAGGCUUCCAAUGAGAAGAUGCAGAUCUUGGGAGAGCCUGAAGUUCAGGCCAGUUGCUGACAGUGCUCGGAGCCCCUUCAUGACCAGCCUCAGCAGGCUAUUGUUGGAGGACUGGUUUGGAUGUGACAACUACAAUUAGACCAGGAAUUAAAC